ACAUCUUGGCCAACAGCAACAUCUUGACUUUUAUAUAUUGACAAAAUUGUAUUUUGAGGGAAUCUUGAAAAAUAUUUGCUUAGCUUCAUGUAUAUUUAUAAGUCCUCUAAGCAAAAGAGAAAUCUUUAAGCAAUGUAGAGUUUACAACUUAAGAUGAUGUGAAAAGAAAUAAAAAACAUCUAUGGGCCACCAGUAUCAGAUUAUUUAAAAAUGUAUGUGUGCAAAGAAAGGAGGCAAAUUUUAGUAUUGAUUUUUAUUUUACCAAGUAUUUACGGGCUACUUUAGAUUAACUACAUAUGACUGUACAACUAAGAGGGCAAACUCUUUGAGAUAGUCAUCUUACAUGGGAUGAUUUGAGAAAUGUUAGAAGGCACAUCUACUUGUAAGAAGGCAUACUUUUUAUAUCCAGCCCGCCACCAGGAAAAAUUUCUACCUAACUGGAGCAGUGUUUCUCCAUAGGGGUGCCACUAACACUGUAGGACGUUUAGUGUCCUUGGUGUUUUAGUCAGGGUUCUCCAGAAAAACAGAGCCUAUAUACAUAUACAUGUAUAGAGAGAUACAGAGAGGGAGAGAGAGGGACAGAGGCACUCAUUAUUAUAGGGAGUUGGCUCUUGCUGUUAUGGAGGCUGGCAAGUCCCAGGGAGCUGCAGUGGGAGUCAGCAAACUGGAGGCCCAGGAGGGCUGAUGGUGCACUUCCAGUCCAACUUUGAAGGUCUGAGAACUGGGAAGAGCAAAUGUUUCAGUUUGAGUCUGAAGGCAGAAAAAAAAUCUCUUCCUUGAGGGAGCGGCACCCUUUUUUGUUCUAUUCAGGCCAUCAACUGAUUGGAUGAGGGUCACCCACAUUCUAGAGGGCAGUCUACUUUACUCAGUCUACCAAUGUAAAUGUUAUUCUUAUCCAGAAACAUUCAGGAUAAUGUUUGACUACAUAUUCGAGCACCCUUUGAUUCAGUCAAGUUGACGUACACAAUAAACCAUUAUAAUAGGCUUUGCUCAGAAAAGUGCUGGUAAUACCCCCGGUCAUUUUGACAGCAUACAGAUACCCCUGGGGGUGAGGUGAGGGUAGUACUUCCAUGAGUAAGAACUGUUGCUGUAAAGUGUCUCCUUUGGGUUAAGACCUUGAGUCUUUAGAAGUUCCUUAACAAAAACAUUGAUGUGUUACUGGAAUGGCUAAUGCCAUUAUCAUUUAACGAUAUAUAUAUGUUUUUUUCCUAAAGAUUUGUUCUUAAAACUUUUAUUAUAAUAAACUUGGGGGGGUGGAAAUUCCAUCACCUUUUGUUAUUAUUUAUUCAUAAUCUAUUUCACAGUCUCAGGUAUGUAUGUAUUCUUACUUAGUUGUAAUUUAAUAUUUUGUGUUUUUCUAAAUAACAUUUUUAAUGUUGCUGCACCAUCACUAAUUGUAACGAUAGUCAUAAUCUACUAGGUGCCUGUUCCACAACUUUUAUCAUUACAAGUAACAUUGCCCUGAAUGUCUUUAGACAUGUAGGGCUUUCCAUGCCUUCUCUGCUCCAUACCCCUUUGCCUUCUUUUCUGUCUUUUUGGGGUCAUUUUCUUUCAUGAACAUUUUAAAAUUAAUCUGUUUAUUUAUUUAGCUAGCUAGUCAUCAGAGAUGAGAGGAGAAUAAAUUUAAGGAUAGGAAGAGUGGAAAGUUAAAGAGCUAGAAUAGAAGCUAUGUGACUUGUUACAUUUCUGAAUAGAAGGUUAUACAGAAGCAUUAGAUUUUUCUUCCAGUAUUGUCUGACUGGAAGAAAAUUUUGUAGUGAUAUGGAUAUUAGGUAAGAAAGCAAAUAUAUUAAGCUAUUUAUGUUAAUUUUGAUUUCCUGACUACUUGCAUUUAAUUUAGCUAGCCCUGCUUAGUUUCACCCAUCUGCACAUGUAUGUAUGUUCUGUUACAUGAAAUAGAAGUAGAAAAAACAGAAAGAAACUUCUCCCUGUAAGUAGCAGGAUGUGAAGGGCCAGAAAUGCAGCUUAGGCAAUAGGCAAUAAGUGAAAAAGCAUAUCUAAAAAAUAUAGUUUGGAGUCUCUAACCUUUUCUAACCCAGUGGUGGCUGUUAGCAUUGACACUGUGGCUACUUUCUGGAAAACAAAGUACAUUGAUUAAAGAUGAUUUUGGUAAUGAAGAAAGUUGUAUUCGAACCAAUUAUUUAUGAAUCGUGGAAAAAGCGCUCAAAGUUUUUAUUUGGUCUUAAUUGUGCCUUCAUGAUCUGUUUACCAUUGUCUUAUGAAAAGAUUCUUUUUUUGCACUUUAUAUGUGUGUGUUUGCAUAUCUUUUUAGGAAUUAAAGAUUAUUCUGAAUAAACUCAAUAUGCACAGUUUUGAUUUCAUCGUGCAGAAAUCGGUAGAAUAUACUUACACAAACCAAGAUGUGGUAAAACCUAGAUGGUACAGCCUAUUACACACCUUGGCUAUAUGAUAUUGCUUAUUGCUCCUGGGCUACAAACCUGUACAACAUGUUACUAUACUGAAUACUGUUGGCACUUGUGAUACAAUGGAAGCUCAUAAAAUGGUGAGAGAAGCAAAUAUCAAGCAGGCAACAGCAGAAAAACAGCUAAAAGAAGCACAAGGAAAAAUUGAUGUACUUCAAGCUGAAGUAGCUGCAUUGAAGACACUUGUAUUGUCCAGUUCUCCAACAUCACCUACGCAGGAGCCUUUGCCAGGUGGAAAGACACCUUUUAAAAAGGGGCAUACAAGAAAUAAAAGCACAAGCAGUGCUAUGAGUGGCAGUCAUCAGGACCUCAGUGUGAUACAGCCAAUUGUAAAAGACUGCAAAGAGGCUGACUUAUCCUUGUAUAAUGAAUUCCGAUUGUGGAAGGAUGAGCCCACAAUGGACAGGACGUGUCCUUUCUUAGACAAAAUCUACCAGGAAGAUAUCUUUCCAUGUUUAACAUUCUCAAAAAGUGAGUUGGCUUCAGCUGUUCUGGAGGCUGUGGAAAACAAUACUCUAAGCAUUGAACCAGUGGGAUUACAACCUAUCCGGUUUGUGAAAGCUUCUGCAGUUGAAUGCGGAGGACCAAAAAAAUGUGCUCUCACUGGCCAGAGUAAGUCCUGUAAACACAGAAUUAAAUUAGGGGACUCAAGCAACUAUUAUUAUAUUUCUCCUUUUUGCAGAUACAGGAUCACUUCUGUAUGUAACUUUUUUACAUACAUUCGAUACAUUCAGCAGGGACUCGUGAAACAGCAGGAUGUUGAUCAGAUGUUUUGGGAGGUUAUGCAGUUGAGAAAAGAGAUGUCAUUGGCAAAGCUGGGUUAUUUCAAAGAGGAACUCUGAUGCUCUGCGUGGGACCAUGCCUGAACUCCCCGAAUAACUGAAAAAUGGCUGAAUAUUUUUAUGGUUACUUGAUAUUUAUUUCCAAGGAGUGAGCCUAAGACUUUUUUCCCCUUUUGCAAAUUGCUCUAAGAAGUACCAUGAUUUCUUUUAAACUGAUCUAUGCUGUGUUUGCUUAUUCUUUAGUUGAACACACUAUGAAGAAUUCCAGGUGUACUAGUGAAUGUAAUUUAUAGUUGCCAAAAAAAAAAAAAACCUGAAAUAAAUAAAUGUUAGAUUGAAUGUGUGUACAUUUUCUCUUCUAGCUCUGACAUGGCAUUUAGGGUUAGCAGAAUGUAUUAAAUAGUAAUUUUCAAACUACACAGUAGCUUCCUUCCUUGUGAGAGGCAAGAAAGAAGUCUGAGUGGAUAGUACUCACUUUCCAAGGCCCCCACCUCUAGAAUGGCUUUAUUUUUAUCUGUUUUCUAUAUUGGGUUUCAAAAAAGAUUUUAUUUGAAGAAAUACUUCUGCUGCUACAAAGUUUGAAAGUUACUAUUUUAAUUAUUCUGCUCUCUGUAACUGAAAGAAUCCCUUUAUUUUGGUUAUUCAUUAAAAUAUAAUAGAAGGCAGUCAGAUUUUAUCCCAGAGAUGUAUUCCUGAGUGUCUUGAUAUAGUGUAUUCAUGUUUUAUAUGUGUUGACCACUAUAUUGUCAUUGGAGGGACAUAGAUGUAAAUGAGUUUGACGUGUGUCAAAGGGGUUUAAAGGGGUGUGGAUUGAAUGAAUGGUACGUGCGAAGUAUAUGCUGAUUAUAGAACCACUUGAUCUCUGCAUUCCAAAUUGUAAAACUGACUCAACUGGAGAAAUUAUAACAAAGAGGUUUGUGGUAGACAUGUAAUAAGUAUAGAAAAGCAAAAAGAAAAGAGAAACUGCUUUAGUUUCUGUUUAGAGAAAGCUGCUGUUAAUAUUUUUGGAUAGUAGCCUUUCAGCUUUCAGAUAUUUUCUACUUACAUAUGCAUAUUUUUGAAACAAAAAGUAGGCUUUUUUUUUGCUUUUUAAACCUAAACAUUAAAUAUAUUUUCCCUUGGGUAAACCUACACAUCCUAAUCCCUGUUUAUAGAAUUUUAACAUAAUUUAAUUGUGUUUGGAGAUGAGGUGGUUUUCAGUUUAUUUUUCAUAUUAUAAUGCUGUGACGAGUAUCCUUAUCUGUACACUUCUGAACAUUGUGGAGUUCUUUCAUGUGGAUGCCUGGAGAUAAAAUUGUGUCGAGAUAUAUAUGUAUUUUUAAAUGUUUGAUCUGCAUUGCUAGAUUGCCAUCCAGAAAAGUUAAUCAAUUUGUAUUCACAGCAGCAGUGUACAAGAGGGCUGGUUUUCUGAAGAUAACAUUUUUUUCAGUCCUGUUCAGAGGUUUGGUCAAUCUUACCUGUAGAUGACUUCAGCCACCAGGCUGGAUGGGAGCCCACAGACAAAAGGACAUUGGUGUAUGUUAUGGUGAAAACCAUCAGUACCAUGCCUAGCUCAAGAAUGUGAAAUUGAACCUGAAAAAAACUUUGAACCUACAAUUUUAUGUUCUGAAAAUAGUUAUUCUAAUGUGAGGGCAUUAAUAAGAAUAUGUACCAUCAAAGCUUCAGAAGAUUUUCCGUACAAACUAAAAUCACUUUUGGAGAAAGUACCUAAAUAAAAAGAGAAACAAAUCCAGGAGAUACUGUACGGUUUGAAAGAAAGGUAAUCAAAUACUCAGAAAAAGUUUGUUGAUGACUUAAAAAGGAUAAAUAAAAAGUAAGACUAAAGAAAAUCAGUAUACCCAUUAAUAAUAAAUCUUUAGUAAUCUAUAAGGGGAAGAAUGCUUUUCAACCUUAUACACUAGAAGCAUGCUCUUUAAAAUUAAUGCAACAGGAUGACGACUUGAUGUAGAAACUAUAUGUGGAAUUAUAGAUUAAAAUGUGAUUGAAACAUAUUUAGAAAAUGUGAUUAUCUUCCUGAUCCUACUCCCUUUAGGAAGAACUUCUUAAACUGGAAGCAGGAAAAAAAAAAACCAUAAAAGAUAACCAUAAAAGAAUAUAAGUUAUGGUAUAUUAUAAAUUCUUAAUUUAGAAAUCGUGCAUCAGUAGUUAGGCAUUGUGGCUCAUGCCUGUAAUCCCAGCACUUUGGGAGGCAGAGGCAGAAGGAUUACUUGAGCUGCUUGAGCCCAGGAGUUUGAGACGGGCCUGGGAAAAAUAGGGAAACUCCAUUUACACACACACACACACACACACACACACACACACUGUGUCCAUGAACUUGGGAGGAUGAGGUGGGAGGAUUGCUUGAGCCCAGGGGUUCAAGUCCAACUUGGGCAACAUAGGGAGACCUUGUCUCUAAAAAAAAAACUAAAGCUAAACUACAAACUGUGAGGCAAUAUCUGCAACAUUUAUAACUAGUAAUAGCUUAGUAUCAAGAAUGUAUGCAGAAAUUCUACAAACCAACAAAAAAGGACAGUGUCACAGAAAAACAGGCAAAAGACUGAACCAGGCCUUCCACACAAUUAGAAGUGCAUGUGGGCCAAUAAACAUUAAGAGGUUUUCAUCUCUCAAUCAGGAAAACGUAAAUCAAGAUGACAAUGACAUGUUCAAAUUCAUUCGAUUGGUGAAAAUGAAGAAACACAAAGUCAAGUUUUGGAGAGGGUUUUAGUCAUUAGGAUCACUCACAUAUUGCUGAUGGGGGUAUCAAUUGGUAUAUCCACUGUGAAAAACCAUUCACUAGAAAAGUUGGGCCAGGCCCAGUGGCUCAUGCCUCUUGGCUUUGGGAGGCCAAGGUAGGAGGAUCACUUGAGCCCAAGAGUUCAAGACCAGCUUGAGCAACAUAGGGAGACCACAUCUGCACAAAAAGAUUUUUUUGAAUUAGCUGGGCAUGGUGGUGCAUGCCUGUGGUCCCAGCUACUUGGGAAGCUGAGGUGGAAGGAUUGCUUAAGCCCAGGAGGUUGAGGCUGCAGUGAAUCAUGAUUGUGCCACUGCACUCUUACCUUGGGUGACAGAGUAAGAUCAUACCUUAAAAAAAAAAAAAAAGUAUACCCAUGGGUCAGCAAUUUCACUUUUCAGUAUAUACUUGAGAAAUGCUUGCACAGGUCCCCCAGAUCACACAUAUAAGAAUGUUCUGGAAUAAAUUAAAAUGUCUAUUUUUAGGAAGGUGUAAUGUGUUCACAGAAUGGGUGAUUAUUACAUGGCAGCAAAAUGAAUGAAUACCAGCUACUUGCAGCACAAUAACUCAGAAUGAAAAAGCAAUUCUGAGAAAACUAUAUGUGACAUGAUACUUUUCUUAUAAAAGUCAAGAACAACUAAAACUGAACAGCUGUUUAGGCAUUGACAUAUGUGACAAAACUUUUAAAAAGUAAUAAAGUUCAAGAUAGUGGUUACCUCUGGAGAGGUAGAGGAGGAGCAAAUCUAUGAGUAAGUCACUGGUAAUGUUUUAGUCCCUGGGUUAGGUGGUGGGUUUUGGGGUGGUUCAUUUGUCAUUAAAAGUAAGUACAUGAGCUGGGUGUAGUGGUGCGUGCUUAUAGUCCCAGCUACUUGGGAGUCUGAGAUAGGAAGAUCCUUGAGGCCAGUUCAAGGCUAUAGUGUGCUAUGAUUUCACCUGUGAAUAGCUACUAUAUUCCAACCUGGGCAACGUAGACCUUGCCCCCCUUUAAAAAAAUUCAAAAACAAAAUAAAUGCAUGGACAAAUGAAUAAGAGAGUUAUGCAUGGAACAUCGGUGGUGUAUUAUGAAUCAAGCAUUAUUACUAGCUCAGUUAUAUGUGCCUUCAUUCCAAAACAAAAAAUAAAAGGUAAGAAAAUUGUUGAAUUGCAUUUGAGAGAGAGGAAAGGAAAGAAUUCAGGUCUGAAUCUUAGGCUUUUGGCUUGAGCUAUUGCAGUUUAUUGAGAUGGGGAAAUACAUGGUGGGGAAAGUUUGGGUAUGUGCAUAACAGAGACAGAAAUUCAGUGUUUGACAGAUCAAGUGUGAGGUGCCCACUGAGCAUCAAAGUGGAUAUGUUAAGCAGGUAUUGGAUGUACAAAUCUAAAUUCAGUAAGGUCAGUCCAGGAGAAAAUUUGGGGAGUAGUUAGCCAUGGGAUCAGAUGGGCGCUUUAGGGACACUUUGGAGAUGAAGUACAGCACUGAGCCCUGAGUUCCUGUGACAGAGAAGCAGCCUGCAAAGACGAAAGGAGGAGCUGUUAGGAAGAGCAAGGCAACAGAAAAGGAAGAACCAGCAUGCUGAUUAUGUUCAGGAGAGUGUUUCUACGCUGAAUUUAAUUGCCAAGAUUACCAAUUCUAAAGAAGAGGAGGACUCUUGGACAAGUUUUUAGAAGUUGGUUUGGAGCUGGGGUGAGAGCCUGGCCUAAUGGAGACAGCUCUGGAUUGGGAGUCACUUAGACCUACAUUCUGGUCUAGGUUUGGCUCCCAAAAACUGGGAAGGUUAGUUAGGUGGCCACUCCUCUCUCUUCAUGGUCUCUCUCAGCUUGAAGACAAUUUACAGUCUUUGACUAAGCAUCCACACUGGAAGAACAAGAUUUGGUUUCUGAACAUUGGGUCUUAGUCCUUAAAAUAACUUGCAACCUGUUACGUCUUCACUUACUCCCAUCGCCACCACAAGAAUCCUGUGUGUUUUUGUUUUGUGCAUCCAGUCUAAAACGGGUCUGCUUUUAUUCAUAGGCUUUUGUUUUCAGUGGUUUUUGUUGUUGCAUUUUUCCCUAGAUAAAAUGUUUUUUCUAUAAGACACUGCUUAAAAGAGUCCAAUGCAGUAUGAAUUUGUAUUUGUGUUUAACUUUUGUGCUUAACAGAUCUGCCAUGGCUGAACUCUCAGUUGCUUAAGCAAAAUUCUGGGGCUUAUUCUAGGUUCCUUUAUUUGUCAUUGUCACUCCCAUUCCAGUUAUCAGCAAAUUCCAUCAGCUGUCUCCGAGACAUCUUAAAUCUGUCUACCUCCCUCCAUGUCCACUGCUACCACUCUGCCCAAGCUAUUAUCAUCUUUCACCUGAACUCCUGCACUAAUGUCUGCUGUCCUUGCAUCCACUCCUGCCCUCCUACAAUCACUGACGGCAGCCGCAGGGAUCUUUAUAAAACGAAAAUCAGAUAAUGUCACUUCCCUGCUUAAAGCCCUUUGAGUGGCUUCCCAUUGCACUUAGAAAAAAAAAAAAAAAAAAAAACUGGCCAGGUGCGAUGGCUCAUGCCUGUAAUCCCAGCACUUUGGGAGGCCGAGGCGGGCGGAUCCCCUGAGGUUGGUAGUUCGAGACCUGCUUGGCCAACAUGGAGAAACCCUGUCUCUACUAAAAACACAAAAUUAGUCAGGUGUGAUGGCGCAUGCCUGUAAUCCCAGCUACUUGGGAGGCUGAGUCAGGAGAAACGCUCGAACCCAGGAGGCAGAGGUUGUGGUGAGUUGACAUCACGCCAUUGCACUCCAGCCUGGGCAACAAGAGUGAAACUCCGUCUGAAAAAAAAAAAAAAAAACCCAAACUCAAUAGAAAAUCAAGUUUUCAUAGUGGUAGUUGUUAACAGAGAAAUAACAAUGAAAGCUUUAAAAAACUCCAUGAAAAUUUGCAAAACUUAAAAAAAAAAUGUAGAAGAGGACUAAACUUGAUAAAAUAUUAAAAGAAUUGAAACCCUUCCUAAAGGCAGCUUCUCAAGGGAGCACAAGUUCACACACAGUUUACUUUUGGAGGAACGUCUGAGGUCAUGAGGACUAGAUUCUAGAGCUACAGGUCUCAGGGACAGUCUCGAGGGAUACAGGGCCCCCAUCACCACAUCCCCAGAUUUAACCGCAGCAGCUCAGCUUUUAUCUGUAUCUGUUGGAGCUCUCUAGGAAAUGUCAAUACCAAAGCAAACCCAAAUCACAACUAGAUUAGAUUACUAUUCAAGAGAAUGAUUCUCUACCGAAACUCUGCAAAAUGGGGAUAUCAAGAGAGUUGGAAAAUGUAAGACGUAAAGACCAUAAUCAGGAAAAUACGCAUCAUAUUUGUUAUUCACUGAGAGGGAGGAAUUUCCACUUAAAUCCUAUUUCCAGCAGCUGGAUUGUGCUCUCAGUGGAGUGCUCUGGAUUCUGAUUAAUAGAGAUUUUCUAGUCCUCCCAGCAACUUCCUUCUCAAUUCUCUUCACUUUCCGCAGAUCUCGGCACCAGGGUUGCAUCUUGUGGGCUCCAUUGUGUUUUCACACAAUGUGCUAUUUGUCCUUCACAGUGUUUUGGUUUAUUUUUCUGUUUGUCCAUCUUGUUUUUGAACAAUUGCCAGCAUUUAAAAAUGAGGAAAUCUAAAAUCUGCAUUUCAAGCUGCUCUUUUUUAAAAUGUGCCGUUUCGACAACACUGAGCCCACAGUCUUGAAUGACAACACUUGGGUGGAGCUGAGUGACUCCACCUGUCGGGUGGCUACACCCUUGCUCAGGGUAUGCACUCCAUGGUUUGCUCUAUGGCCCACCAUCCUGGAUUGUCUCCCUGACACCAAGGCUAAGGGACCCACUUUACUCACUUAUCUGCUGGGCCUUGGAAGUAUUUCAGUUCGGAACCCCAAUUCUAACCUUAGCUUCUCAGGCCAUUAAAUGAAAUCUCAUUUCUAUGAUGCUUCCUGUCACAUCACUGUGCUGCUGAGAACAUGAAGUCUGUGGGUGAAUUGGUGGACGGGAUCCAGAAUCAUUACUUGGCAGUGGAUUAUAGUGUGAUGACUCAUUUCCGGUGGUCUCCAGGAGACUUGGCUGGGAGCUUCUCUUGGAGUCUAGGGUUAGCCAGAGGCUACAUGUUUUAGGCAUCUUAAUUCAUAUUUUAUCUAAAGGCAUAUAAAUCCUUAAAAAAAAUCAUUUGACUUCAUCCUUGCUCCCUACAUCCAGCCAGUAACCAUUGCUUUGUUUUACAUCGCGUGCUUCAGGCUUUACUACAGCCUACCUGGAUUUUGCAGUAGCUUCUUAAACUGCUUAAACUUUGGAUAUUGCCCCAGCCAACACAUUCUGCCACAGAGAUCUCUCUGAGUUAAAUGGGAUUGUAUCAUGCCCCACACCCAAGCAGAUAGAAACUGUCAAUAGAUACACUUAGAAUGAAUAUGCAUGGAAUCAAAUUACAUUCAGAAUCUACCACUAUAGGUAGUGAAUACAACAGGAUAGCAGAGGCUGGGAAGGGUAAUGGGGGUUGGGGGGUGGGAGGAUAAAGGGGUUGGGUAAUGGGUGUAAAAAUCUAUAGAAGGAAUAUGAUCUGUUGUUUGGUAGCACAAUAGGGUAAAUACAGUUAAUAAUUUAUUGUAUAUUUCACAAUAAAGGAGUGGAUUUGGAAUGUUCUCAACACAAAUGAUAAAUGUUUGAGGUGAUGGAUACCCCAAUUACCCUGAUUUGAUCAUUAUACGUUGUAUGUUUGUAUCAAAAUAUCAUAUGUACCCCAUAAAUAUGUACAACUAUUAUGUAUCCAUAAAAAUUGGAAAUAAACUACCACCAUCUUUCUUCAGCCUAUUUUCCUAUCUCCUCUCGCACCAUACUAGGCACACAAUCUCUGUACCUGUGCUGUCUUCCAAGCCAUUGCUCAUGUUUUAAGAAAUAUACUUAUUGUUUAAUAUAUCCUGUACCACUGUAGGAUGACUGUAGUUAACAAUAAUGUGUAGUUUCAAAUAGCUAAUAGCUGGAAGGAAGUUGUUGAAUGUUUCCAACAUAAAGAAAUGAUAAGUGUUUGAGAUGAUGGAUAUGCUAAUUACCCUGAUCUGAUCACUACACAUUAUAUGUAUGGAAAUAUCAUUGUGUACCCCAUGAAUAUGGGCAAUUAUUAUUUGUUAAUUAAAAAAAUAAAAAAAAGACCCACCCACUGUUUAA